AGUUUCUUCUAGGAAUUCGGAGCCUCCCCUGCAGCGACUCGGAAGAUUCGAGGCGGCGGGGGACAAGUCGGCGCCCCAGAGCGGACGAGUCACCAGGUGUCAAGAUGCUGCAAGUACAUAGGACUGGACUGGGCAGGCUGGGGGUCAGCCUCUCCAAGGGUCUUCACCACAAAGCUGUGUUGGCCGUCCGGAGGGAGGAUGUGAACGCCUGGGAGAGAAGGGCCCCGCUAGCUCCCAAGCACAUCAAAGGCAUCACCAAUCUGGGAUACAAGGUCUUGAUACAGCCUUCGAAUCGGCGGGCCAUUCAUGAUAAGGACUAUGUCAAAGCUGGUGGCAUUCUUCAGGAGGAUAUUUCUGAAGCUUGUCUAAUUUUAGGAGUUAAAAGACCUCCAGAGGAAAAAUUAAUGUCCAGGAAGACUUAUGCAUUUUUCUCCCACACAAUAAAAGCUCAGGAGGCCAAUAUGGGCUUGUUGGAUGAGAUUCUAAAACAGGAAAUUCGCCUUAUUGAUUAUGAGAAAAUGGUGGAUCAUAGAGGAGUACGGGUAGUGGCAUUUGGACAGUGGGCUGGUGUGGCAGGAAUGAUCAACAUUUUACAUGGAAUGGGUUUAAGGCUCCUUGCUUUGGGACAUCACACACCUUUUAUGCACAUUGGCAUGGCUCAUAACUACAGGAAUAGCAGUCAGGCUGUGCAAGCUGUCCGUGAUGCUGGCUAUGAAAUAUCUUUGGGUUUGAUGCCUAAGUCAAUAGGACCCUUAACAUUUGUGUUCACAGGAACUGGUAAUGUUUCUAAGGGAGCCCAAGCAAUCUUUAAUGAGCUACCUUGUGAAUAUGUGGAGCCCCAUGAAUUAAAAGAAGUUUCCCAAACUGGAGACCUCAGAAAAGUGUAUGGGACGGUGUUAAGUCGUCAUCAUCAUCUUGUCAGGAAAACAGAUGCUGUGUAUGAUCCUGCAGAGUAUGACAAACAUCCGGAGCGCUACAUAAGUCGUUUUAAUACUGAUAUUGCACCCUAUACAACUUGCUUAAUUAAUGGAAUCUACUGGGAACAAAACACUCCUCGCCUCCUAACCCGCCAAGAUGCUCAGAGUCUCCUGGCUCCGGGCAAGUUCUCACCUGCUGGUGUGGAAGGCUGCCCUGCAUUACCACACAAACUCGUGGCAAUAUGUGACAUUUCAGCUGACACAGGAGGGUCUAUAGAGUUUAUGACUGAGUGUACAACAAUAGAGCAUCCCUUUUGCAUGUAUGAUGCAGACCAGCAUAUUAUUCAUGACAGUGUUGAAGGCUCGGGGAUCCUGAUGUGUUCCAUUGACAAUUUGCCGGCACAGCUCCCAAUUGAAGCUACAGAAUGCUUUGGAGACAUGCUUUACCCUUAUGUUGAAGAAAUGAUAUUAUCAGACGCGACACAGCCUCUUGAAAGUCAGAAUUUUUCUCCUGUGGUGAGAGAUGCAGUGAUUACAUCCAACGGUACAUUACCUGAUAAAUAUAAAUAUAUCCAGACACUCCGGGAGAGCAGGGAACGUGCUCAGUCACUUUCAAUGGGCACCAGGAGAAAGGUUUUGGUUCUUGGAUCUGGCUACAUAUCUGAGCCUGUAUUAGAAUAUUUAUCAAGAGAUGGCAAUAUAGAAAUAACAGUAGGAUCUGACAUGAAGAAUCAAAUUGAACAGUUAGGCAAGAAAUAUAAUAUUAAUCCUGUUAGCAUGGACAUUUGUAAACAAGAAGAGAAGCUGGGCUUCUUGGUGGCAAAACAGGAUCUUGUCAUCAGCUUGUUGCCUUAUGUAUUGCACCCUCUUGUGGCCAAGGCCUGCAUCACAAACAAAGUUAACAUGGUCACUGCAAGCUACAUCACACCAGCACUAAAAGAAUUGGAAAAGAGUGUGGAAGAUGCUGGCAUCACAAUCAUUGGUGAAUUGGGAUUGGACCCUGGUCUGGAUCACAUGUUAGCAAUGGAAACAAUAGAUAAAGCCAAGGAAGUGGGAGCCACGAUUGAAUCAUAUAUUUCCUACUGUGGUGGGCUUCCAGCCCCUGAACAUUCAAACAAUCCAUUGAGAUAUAAAUUUAGCUGGAGUCCAGUGGGAGUUUUGAUGAAUGUAAUGCAGUCUGCCACCUAUCUGCUCGAUGGAAAGGUUGUGAAUGUUGCAGGAGGCAUCUCCUUUCUUGAUGCCGUUACGUCCAUGGAUUUUUUUCCAGGAUUAAAUUUGGAAGGCUAUCCUAACAGAGACAGUACGAAAUAUGCUGAGAUUUAUGGCAUUUCUUCUGCUCACACUUUGUUGCGGGGGACACUGAGAUAUAAGGGAUAUAUGAAAGCUUUGAAUGGAUUUGUAAAAUUAGGUCUUAUAAACAGAGAAGCGCUUCCUGCCUUUAGACCUGAGGCCAACCCUCUCACCUGGAAACAACUCCUCUGUGACCUAGUUGGGAUUUCACCCUCCUCUGAGCAUGAUGUGUUGAAGGAAGCUGUUCUUAAGAAACUAGGAGGAGACAAUACCCAGUUGGAGGCUGCUGAAUGGUUGGGCUUACUUGGGGAUGAACAAGUUCCUCAGGCAGAGUCCAUUCUGGAUGCCCUCUCCAAGCAUUUGGUCAUGAAGCUUUCCUAUGGUCCUGAAGAAAAAGAUAUGAUUGUGAUGAGAGACAGCUUUGGAAUCAGACAUCCUUCUGGACAUUUAGAACAUAAAACGAUUGAUCUUGUGGCUUAUGGGGACAUCAAUGGCUUUUCAGCCAUGGCUAAAACCGUGGGGUUACCCACCGCCAUGGCAGCCAAAAUGUUGCUUGAUGGUGAAAUUGGAGCCAAAGGCCUAAUGGGGCCCUUUUCAAAGGAGAUCUAUGGACCAAUAUUGGAGCGAAUUAAAGCAGAAGGCAUUAUAUAUACUACACAGAGUACAAUUAAACCAUAAUUGGGAAUUAUAUUUUGUUUUUUUCUUCCCAGGCAAUACACCUCUGAACAUGUGUGUGAUAAAUGGGUUUGCUAAUGUGCUGUUUUAAAGUAUAAAGCAUAAUAUGUUUUGGUUAACACAAUGUACUUUUUGAACUAUAAAUCUUUAUUUUAAUAUGGAAAUGUUUGGAACAGGAGAUGCAAGCCACUAACAGAGAACUUUAAUAAUUCUACCCUGUAUUUUAUAAAUACGUAUGUGAAAGUGAUGAUCAUGCUAUUUGUUAAUUUAUUGUGCCACUUUUUUUCUUUUGUUUUUUUUUUGUUGUUGUUGUUUUUUGAGAUGGAGUCUCGCUCUGUCACCCAGGCUGGAGUGCAGUGGCGCGAUCUCGGCUCACUGCAAGCUCCGCCUCCUGGGUUCACGCCAUUCUCCUGCCUCAGCCUCCCAAGUAGCUGGGACUACAGGCACCCGCCACCACGCCCGGCUAAAUUUUUUGUAUUUUUCAGUAGAGACGGGGUUUCACCAUGUUAGCCAGGAUGUCCACUUUUUUCUUAAAUGAACAUAUUGUCUUAUAACCAGCAAAUGAAGUUUUACUUUUUUAGUCAGAAAAAAUUUCGUCAUAAAGCUAUAUUUUUAUAUUUUUAAAAUUGAUACAGUUAGAUACCUUCAGAUUACCUAAGUUAAGUUUUUGCCAAAAUGCUAUUUUAUGCCCUUUUUGUAAAGUUAUGAUUUAUUUUGUAAAUAUAGUUCCUUAUAGUUUUCUCUUGAGUGUUUGGACAUGAGAAUAGAUAAGAUUAAAUUACAAUUUACAAGAUCACUUCAUUAGGCACAGGAAAAGUAUUUAACAAAAUUCAACACCCUUUCACAAUAAAAAAUAAAAAAUAAAAAACCCUCAACAAACUAGGAAUAGAAGGAAACUUCCUCAACCUGAUAAAGGGCAUCUAUGAAGAACCCAUGGUUAGCAUCAUACUUAAUGGUGAAGGACUGGAUUAUUUCCCCCUGAGAUCAGAAACAAGACAAGGAUGUCUGCUUUGGCCAUUUCUAUUCAACUUGUACUGGACAGUCAAGAAAGGGCAAUUAGGCAAGAAAAUAAAAUAAAAGUCAUCUAGGUUGGAAAGGAAGAAGUAUAACUAAAUAGAGAUGGGAGACGAUAUGGUGGUUUUGUGCAUAGUAAUCCAAGGGAAAACUAUAGAAAAUCCAAAGGCAUGAUUUAUUAAUAAAUAAAUUCAGCAAAGUUACAGGAUACAGGAUUAAAUAUGCAGAAAUUGGUUAUCUUUCAAUAUAGUAUCAAUGAAUAAAUCAAAAAUGAUGUUAAGAAAACAAUUUAAUUUUCAACAAUGGUCAAGCUUGGUGGCUUGUGCCUGUAAUCCCAACACUUUGGGAGUCUGAGGCAGAAAGACUGCUAGAGGCCAGGAGACCAGCCUGGGAAACAGUGAGAUCCCAUCUCUACAAAAACAAACAAACAAAAAACAACAAGCAAACAAAAAACAGCUGGAUGUGAUGACACUCAUCUGUCGUCUCAGCUACUCAGAGGCUGAGGUGUAAGGAUGGCUUGAGCCCCAAAGUUCGAAGCUGCAAUGAGCUAUAACUGGGUCACUGCAAUCCAGCCUGGAUGACAGAGUUAGACCUUGACUCAAAAAAAACAAAAAAGAAAAGAAAAAAAUUGACAGCAUCAGAAAGAGUAAAAUACCAAUAUAAUUGAGGGUCCAGAAAUAUUGAUCACAUUUAUCAUCAACUGACUUUUGAAAAUAGUGCUAAGACAAUUCAAUGGGGGCAAAAUAGUCUUUUUCAUUAAAUGAUGCUUGGAAACAUGGAUAUCCACAUGCAAAAUAAUGAAAUUGGACUCCUACCUCAUAUUGCAUAUAAAAAUUAACUCAAAGUUGACCUAAGAUCUAAAUGUAAGAGCUAAUAUUGUAAGUAUCUUCAAAGAAAACAUGGCGUAAAUCUUUCUGACUUUGAAUUAGGCAAUGAUUUCUUAAAUAAAUGACACUAAAAACACAAGCAACAAAAGAAGAAAAUAGGUAAAUUAAAAUUAAAACCAUUUGUGUUUCCAAGGACAAUAUCAAGAAAGCAAAAAUACAACCCACAGAAUGAGAUAAUUUUUUUUAAAAUCAUGUAUUAGUUAAGGGAGGAAUUUGUAUUUAGAAUAUGUAAAGAACUGUUACAAUAAUAAUUAAAAGGCAUAUAAUUCAAUUUUUAAAAAUCAACAAGAGAUCUGAAUUAACAGUUCUCCAAAGAAGAUACACAAAAGGCCAAUAAGCACAUGAAAAGGUUCUCAACAUCACUAGCCAUCAGGGAAAUGCAAAUGAGAUCUACAAUGAGAUAUCACUUAACACUCACUGGAAUAGAUAUAUAAUCAAAGUGAUAAUAUCAAGUGUUGGUGAGGAUGCAGAGAAAUUGGAACCCUCAUGCACUGUUGGUGGAUACCCACGUGAUAUAAAAACAAAUGUCUACACAAAAACUUGUGCACAGAUGUUCUUUGCAGCAUUAUUUAUAAUAGCCCAAAAUUGAAACAGCCCUAAUUUCUAUCAACUAACAAGUGAAUAAACAAAACGUGGCAUAUCCAUACAAGGAAUAUUAUUCAGCAAUAAAAAAAGAGAUGAAGUACUGAUAUGCACCACAACAUGGAAAAACCUUGAAAACAUAUCAAGUGAAGAAUGCCAGACAUGAAAGGCCACAUAUUAUAUGAUUUCAUUUAUAUGAAAUGUCCAGAACAGGCGAAUAUAUAUAGAGAGAAGGCAGAUUAGUGGUUGCUUAGGCUGAAGGGUUGGGGAGGACAAAGGGGUGACUGCUAAUUAGUAUGGGGUUUCUUUUUUGGGGUGAUGUAAACGUUGUAAAGUUGAUUGUGGUAAUGGUGGCACAACUCUGAAUAUACUAAAAACCACUGAAUUGUAUACUUUGAAUGUUUGAACUGUGUGGUAUGUAGAUUUUAUCUCAAGUUGUUAUAAAAAAUUAAAUUACAAA